CUCUUUCUCGACUCCAUCUUCGCGGUAGCUGGGACCGCCGUUCAGUCGCCAAUAUGCAGCUCUUUGUCCGCGCCCAGGAGCUACACACCUUCGAGGUGACCGGCCAGGAAACGGUCGCCCAGAUCAAGGCUCAUGUAGCCUCACUGGAGGGCAUUGCCCCGGAAGAUCAAGUCGUGCUCCUGGCAGGCGCGCCCCUGGAGGAUGAGGCCACUCUGGGCCAGUGCGGGGUGGAGGCCCUGACUACCCUGGAAGUAGCAGGCCGCAUGCUUGGAGGUAAAGUCCAUGGUUCCCUGGCCCGUGCUGGAAAAGUGAGAGGUCAGACUCCUAAGGUGGCCAAACAGGAGAAGAAGAAGAAGAAGACAGGUCGGGCUAAGCGGCGGAUGCAGUACAACCGGCGCUUUGUCAACGUUGUGCCCACCUUUGGCAAGAAGAAGGGCCCCAAUGCCAACUCUUAAGUCUUUUGUAAUUCUGGCUUUCUCUAAUAAAAAAGCCACUUAGUUCAGUCA